GAGAAAAUGGCGGCCCCCAGACCGCACUGCGGGCGUCGCGGCAGGUGAAGCGGUGGUGGCAGAGGCGCCUGCGGUUACUGGCCGGGCCGACGGGUCCUGAGUCUCCAGAGCUCGGUUCUUACAUCCCCGCGUCCCCAGGUUUAGCCUGAGCAGGGUUGUGGAAGGCCGGGACCCAUUGACAGCACGAUGGUGACGGAGCAGGAGGUGGAUGCCAUCGGGCAGACGCUGGUGGACCCCAAGCAGCCCCUGCAGGCCCGCUUCCGGGCGCUGUUCACGCUGCGUGGGCUCGGCGGCCCAGGCGCCAUUGCAUGGAUCAGCCAGGCCUUCGAUGACGAUUCCGCCCUGCUCAAGCACGAGCUGGCCUACUGCCUGGGCCAGAUGCAGGAUGCCCGCGCCAUCCCCAUGCUGGUGGACGUGCUGCAAGACACCCGUCAGGAGCCCAUGGUGCGCCAUGAGGCAGGGGAGGCCCUGGGGGCCAUCGGGGACCCGGAAGUUCUGGAGAUCCUGAAGCAGUAUUCCUCGGACCCCGUCAUCGAGGGCGACCACUUGGCCAAGGAUGCCCCAGGGAUGAGGAAGGCGAGGGCGACAAUCUGGACAGACACUUGCUGCGCCCCAUUUGGCAAAACGGCGACAACCAGCUUUGCUCACCCGCUUCCAUCCCGGGCCUUGAGCCCCUGAGCCGGCCUGACCCCCUUUCUCUGAACCCCCACGUCCAGUCCCUCUGCCAAGACCCCUCUGAACCCACCCAGUGCCCUCUACCUCUGAUACCUUGUCCUGGCCCACCAGACCUCUUCAGAGAUCUCCUGCUACCUUCCAACAUUUCUUCUUUUUUUUUUUUGAGACGGUGUCUCGCUCUGUCGCCCAGGCUGGAGUGCAGUGGGCGCGAUCUCGGCUCACUGCAAGCUCUGCUUCCCAGGUUCAUGCUAUUCUCCUGCCUCAGCCUCCAGAGUAGCUGGGACUACAGGCGCCUGCCACCACGCUCAGCAAAUCUUUUCGUAUUUUUAGUAGAGACGGGGUUUCACCAUGUUAGCCAGGAUGGUCUCGAUCUCCUGACCUCGUGAUCCACCCGCCUUGGCCUCCAAAGUGCUGGGAUUACAGGCGUGAGCCACCGCGCCUGGCCCAAAAAUGAAACAAAUUUUUAUUUUAUUAGUUUUUUCUUUAUAGAGAUGAAGUCCCGCUCUGUCGCCCAGGCUGGUGUUGAACUCCUGGGCUCAAGCGAUCCUCCUGCCUUGGUCUCCCUAACUGCUGGGAUUAGGGGCAUGAGCCGCUUCGGCCGGCCCGUCAUUCCUUUUUGUGGCUGAGUCACGUUCCGUGGUGUGGACGGCCCAUGCUGUGUCCACUCACUGUGGCUGGAUGCUUGAAUUGUCUCUGCUUUUUAGCUGUUAUGAGUUAUGCCGCCACGGACAUGCAUGUUCCUUUCUCCCCUGCCACUUCUUGUCCACAUCCCACCCCGACCCUCAGUCUCUCCUCCUCCGGGGCAGCCGGGGGUACGUGUGACACUCAAUUCUGCUGUUCUGUUCCAUGCUUAAAGCUCUCACGAUAUCUCAUCACCUUUAGGACAAAAUCCCAAGCCCUUACAGUGGCCCGCAGGCCUUACCUGGUCAGGUGGGGCCGCACAUGUUCCUUUGGCCCUCACCCCUCCCGCAGGGUCCUGCCUCAGGGCCUUUCCACCGCUGCUUCCCCAUCCCCGGGUCUCCACCUGAUUCCCUCCCUAAGCUGGCUUAGGUCUCUGCCUCCACAUCACCUCCUCCCUGAGGCCCUCCCCAGCCCUCCAGUCCCCCGGUCACUCACAAGUCAGCCACCCCUGCUGGCUUACUUCCUGCCUGGAAUGAUGGGUUAGUCACCCUGCCAGUGUCUCUCUCCCCUGCUAAGCUGCCAUCCCGGGGGGUGGGGAAGGGCCCCUGCGACCCCCCAGGGCCAACCCGCUGCCUGAU